GCAGCGGCGGUGGGAGGAGUGGGGGACCUGGAGGGAGGUGGUGAAAUAGAAUGGUCCUGGGGGACGGGACUCCAGGGGUUUGACGAUUAGGCGUCAAGACUGACUUAGACCUGGGAAGAAAACCAGAGGCAGUCGAGCAGAGAGGCCAAACGCCAGGCAGGGCGAAGUCAGCCGGAGAUGGAGUGGAAACUGGAGCGCACCGCGCCUCGGAGGGUCCGCACGGAAGAGGAGAUGCUGUGGGAAAGUAUCAUGCGUGUGCUCUCCAAAGACUUGAAGCAGAAGAGAAGUCAAGAUUCCGCCAACGUACUCGAUUCAGUUAAUGCUACGUAUUCUGACUUUAAGAGCAACUUUGCGAAGAGGCUGUCCGCAGAGGUUCCUGUUGCGAGUAGCCCCAUUACCACAAGGUGGCAGCAAAGUCAAACUAGGGCUCUGUCCUCUGAUUCCUUUGGGGAAGAGCAGUCAACCACCUACCUCCCAGAAGCUUCCGGAUCAGUGCUGAAGACACCGCCUGAGAAAGAGACCUUGACUCUAGGAUCCCGCAAAGAACAACUGAAGACCCCCAGCAAAGGAAUUUCUGAAACAAGUAACUCUGCUCUCCAUUUUUGCAAGGCACCUCAUGCAAUGGACAGAGACUGGAAAGAAAGUGUUGCCUCAAAAGGGCAGAAAUGCCUAAAACAACUCUUUGUAACCCAGAACGUGGUUCAGCAGGCUAAUGGAAAAAUGCAGCUCUGUGAGCAAUCCGAAUGUGUUUGGAAAGGCUGCAAAGAUGGAGUCAGAGAUGAAUCCUUCCAUCUUAAAAGUUCUGGUGAUAUAAACGAUUCCAUACUCCAACCAGAGGUGAAGAUUCAUAUUACUGGUCUUCGAAAUGACUACUAUCUGAAUAUCCUAGAUUGGAGUUUUCAGAAUCUUGUUGCCAUAGCCCUGGGCUCUGCUGUAUACAUCUGGAAUGGGGAGAACCACAAUGGGAUUGAAAACAUAGACUUAAGUCUCACUUGUAACUAUAUCUCUUCUGUGUCCUGGAUAAAAGAGGGAACUUGCCUGGCAGUUGGCACCAGCGAGGGAGAAGUGCAAUUAUGGGAUGUGGUAACUAAAAAGCGGCUGAGAAAUAUGCUUGGUCAUUUGUCAGUAGUUGGGGCUCUGAGCUGGAAUCACUUUAUCCUCAGCAGUGGGUCAAGACUGGGGCGUGUUUAUCAUCACGAUGUUCGGGUAGCCCAGCAUCAUGUUGGAACACUUCGCCACAAGCAAGCUGUGUGUGCUCUGAAGUGGUCACCGGAUGGCAGGCUGCUUUCCAGCGGCUGCAGUGAUGGACUGCUGACAAUAUGGCCCCACGAUCCAGGUGCCAGUGCACAGGGCCAACCGCUGAAAGUCAUAACCCAGUCUACGGCAGUCAAGGCCAUGGAUUGGUGUCCCUGGCAGUCUGGGGUCCUUGCCAUUGGAGGAGGAAUGAAGGAUGGACGCUUACACAUCUUGGAUAUAAAUGCUGGGAAGAGCAUCCAGACCCCAAGCACAAACUCACAGAUUUGUUCCUUAAUCUGGCUACCUAAGACAAAGGAGAUUGCAACUGGUCAAGGUACUCCCAAGAAUGAUGUGACUGUGUGGACCUGUCCCACUGUGUCCAGGUCAGGUGGGUUUUUUGGCCACAGGGGCAGAGUGCUGCACCUGUCUUUGAGUCCAGACCAGACCCGGGUGUUUUCUGCUGCAGCUGAUGGGACGGCCUCUGUAUGGAAUUGCUACUAGCACCCAGCCCCUCUAGGUUUCAGUUUCCUUAUUUCUGAGUGAAGAUGAUGAUGUUGGCUAUGUCUUCUCCAUGGGGUUUUUAUGAGUAUCAAACAAGUUGAAAUACUCUUCUUGAUGUGAAUGCCUGUUCUCCUGUUCUUCUUUUGCAGAUUGCUUUACUUGCUCUGCUUCCCAGAGAUCCGCUUCUUUUCUUCUCUGCUUUCUUCUUUCUGCCCCUCUUCCUCCCCCUCCUCUUCUUCCUCCCAUUCUUACCCCUUUCUAGAGAUUCAUUUUCACUACUUUAUUCAGAAUAACAUCUAUAGCAAAGAUUUCUACUUCUUUCCCGUAUGACUUUUCUCCCCAGCUCCAAACCUCAUAUUUCUGAUUGCCUCAGGAUAGUUCCCUUUUGAGAUACUUUCCUGUCUUUAGCUCAAUCUCAACACAUUGAAAACACAACUCAUUCACUUGAAAAACACUUACUAAAAUCUCACUAUAUGCUAGGCAGUAUGUUAAGCAUGCAUAUUGCUCUCUCUAAAAAUCAGUUCUGUAGGAAUCCCUUUCCCCUCCUGAUGGUCUCAUCCUUAUCCUGGUCUCCCACUCAGGGAACCUCCUGAUUAUUCUGCUCUGUGCUUCCUCAGUUCACCCUUUGCUCUCUUUUCUUUUGCUUCACCUAGUCACAUCCUGUGUGCCUGACAGCCAGUCUGCUGUAAUUGUCUUAGAACUGAUCCUCUUGACUCCACACCACUGCUAGGUUGAACAUCUAAAAGUCCUGUGCUGAUCCUCUCAGUCCCCUGCUCAUCAACUCUCAAGGACAACCUAUUACCAAACACCUUUGACCUCAACCUCUGGAGUCCUCAGCCCAGGACUUGAAGUUAGGAGAUCUUUUUUUGCCUUGGCUCUGCCAUAAAUACACCCUGUAACCUUGGAUGUGUUGCAACAUCUGCAAGGAUAGGAAUUUGAUCACUGCUAAGGUUCCUUCAAACUUGAUCAGUUCGCUGUUCUGUCUUUUGAAUGUUAAUUCACAUUCAUCUCCUAUAUUAAGACUUUGGCUAAGUCUUGUGAUUUCUUGCCUUAUUGGAGCUUUUCUUCUAAUCUGAAUUCUUGCUUCUCUCUCCUUUUCCUUUACACACCCACACAAGUCCUAACCUCUCCAGGAAGUGUUUUGAAAUGAUGUUACCUGGGUUUGAGUUCUUGGCAUUAGCCUGUAUCAUCUAUUUGGUAUUAUUAUACUAUUAUAGCUGUUUAAAAAAAUCUUUUAUUACUGUUUG